GAGAGCACAUCCUAGAAGAGAGGAGGCUGGAGGCAGAAGUCAGGAAGGAGACUUCUGAAUGAACAGUGAAUCUAUUACUGAGAAAAACCAGGGGUGGCCUGUGUAUAUAGGUCGCAAUUAGACACCGGCUUCUGGAAGAGCUUUCCCAGAGACAGAUUGAAAUAUUCCCCAGUAGACAUGGCUGCAAAUUGCACAUCCUCAUGGAGUCUAGGAGAAUCCUGCAACAGCCCUGGGUCAGAGCCACCACAGUCCAUGCCAUCCCCAGCAACUCAACUUGGAAAUCAUGACAGUGAUCCUGAGACUUGUCACGUGAACUUCAGGAUGUUCAGCUGCCCGAAGGAGUCGGACCCCAUCCAGGCUCUGAGGAAACUCACUGAGCUGUGCCAUCUGUGGCUGAGGCCCGACCUCCACACCAAAGAGCAGAUCCUGGACAUGCUGGUGAUGGAGCAGUUCAUGAUCUCCAUGCCCCAGGAGCUCCAGGUCUUAGUCAUGAUGAACGGUGUGCAGAGCUGCAAAGACCUGGAGGACCUGCUACGAAAUAACAGAAGACCCAAGAAAUGGUCUGUAGUCAGUUUUCUUGGCAAGGAAUAUCUUAUGCAGGAAUCAGAUGUGGAGAUGGCUGAAGCCCCCGCCAGUGUCAGAGAUGAUCCGAGACACGUGUCCAGCCAGCGGACCUCCUCUGUGAACCAGAUGUGUCCGGAGGAAGGCCAGGCCAGCCAAGAGCUGCAGACCCUGCCCAGGGUCCCUGCACUGUUCAGGAGGCAGGAAGAGGACUUCCUGCUGCCAGAGACUACUGUCAUGAAAGGUGACCCAAAGGCUCUGAGACCCAAGCCGACCUUGGAGAAGGACCUGGAGGAAGACAGGGAGGAGAACCCAGGACUUACAUCCCCAGAGCCUCAGCUUCCAAACAGUCCCACAGGGGUGGUGGGAGCAAAGGAGGGGAAGGAACCCCAAAAAAGAGCCUCUGUGGAAAAUGUGGAUGCUGACACACCUUCUGCCUGCGUUGUGGAGAGAGAAGCUUCGACUCACAGCGGGAGCAGAGGAGACGCUCUGAAUCUGAGAGGUCUCAAAAGAAGCAAACCAGACGCCACCUCCAUUUCCCAAGAAGAGCCUCAAGGAGAAGCCACACCUGUGGGCAACAGAGAAUCCCCGGGACAAGCUGAGAUCAAUCCAGUUCAUUCCCCAGGCCCUGCGGGCCCAGUCAGUCACCCCAGUGGCCAAGAAGUCAAGGAACUGCUGCCCUUUGCAUGUGAGGUGUGCGGCAAGAGGUUUAAGUAUCGCGGCAAGUUAGCCGUCCACACGAGAUCACACACAGGCGAGAGACUCUUUCAGUGUAAUCUCUGCGGGAAGCGCUUCAUGCAGCGCAUAGGCCUGCAAUUUCACCAGCGAACCCACACUGGCGAGAGGCCCUACACGUGUGACAUCUGCCAGAAGCAGUUCACCCAGAAGUCCUACUUGAAGUGUCACAAGAGAAGCCACACAGGGGAGAAGCCCUUCGAAUGUAAAGACUGCAAGAAAGUUUUCACCUACAAGGCAAAUCUGAAGGAGCACCAGCGCAUCCACUCUGGAGAGAAACCCCACAAAUGUUCCAAGUGUCCAAGAGCCUUCGGUCGGCCGGCGACCUUAAGACGCCACCAGAAAACACAUCGAGAAGCCACUUCACAGUGACUUCACCAUCGGGUCUGUCUUCUGCACCAAGAAAGUGUGAAUGAAGAUUUUUCACCGAUGUUGUCAGAUGACGUUUGACAGAUGAAGGGCGCCUGGCACGCAGAGGAGUGCCCUAGAUAGGAAUUCCUAGGAUGUUUGUUUAAAUCUUUUUCCUCCCCGGGGGAAUUUUGGUUUUUGUUUCAUUAUUUCUAUUGUUUUAGGUUUAUUUUGGUUUGUGUUGCUGUUCUUUCAAUAAACAUCUUAUUAGUUUUCAAUAUUUUG